GAGGAGGCGCGAGGGCGGAAGGGGACACUUGACUUUCCCUCUGGUCUCUUCGGGGGCCGCGGGGAAGGGUCGGCGCGGACGGAGCUCGGGGCAUGUGGGACCCCCGCGCGUUCGAGCGGCGCUGGCGGGCCGAGUUCCCCGGGGCGGAGGCGCCGGUCCCGAGGCUGGAGUCGGUGCGGGACGCGGAGCGGGAGCUGGAGCGCCGCAGACUCAACCUGGAGCGGCUGCAACAGGUGCUGGCGGAGGAGCAGCUCAAAGCCUCGCUCCCGCAGGCCGCGCUGGCCCGGGGCGGCGGCGGAGACUCCGGGGAGCCCGGGCGCCCCGACCCCGAGGCCGAGUCUCCCCGCGGGGACCCCGGGCGCCCCGACCCCGAGGCCGAGUCUCCCCGCGGGGACCUGCCCGCCGGGCCCGGGGCGGCCGGAGAAGCCGGCGGGGGAAGGAGCUGGGCCGACGCCGUCCACCGGCAGCUCCUGCAGCCCCAGCUGCGGUUCCGGGCCCGGGAGGACGACGCGCCCCUCGGGGACCCCCAGGCGGCUCCCGGCACGGACGAGGGGGGCGACGGCGGCGACCACGACUUCGAGAUGGUGGAUUUCAACGAGAAGUUCAUCCUCAGCCACUGGCUGGUGGCCCCUUGCCGGUUCGGGACCCGCGAGCGGGCGCGCAGCCCCCGCCGCUGGAUGCACCUGAUCCCCGGGGGGCGGCGGCCGCAGCGGGGGACCCGCGACCUGGAGCAGCGGGAGGCCGAGGCCAAGGGCCGCCCGGGCUCGCCCCUCGCCGCGGAGGAGACCCCCGGGCGCGAGCACCUGCCCCCGUGGCGGCGCCGCAGGUUCCUGCGGGUGCCCGAGCGGGACUCGCCCGGCCACAGCUCGCCGGAGAGAGACAGCGACGGCAGCCGGCACAGCUCCGACCGCGAGGACGACUUCUCCGCAGACUUCAGCUACGGGACGGACGAGUACGACGGAGAGGGGAAUGAGGAGCAGAAGGGGCCCCCGGAGGGCUCAGAGACCAUGCCGUACAUCGAUGAGUCGCCCACCAUGUCCCCGCAGCUCAGCGCCCGCAGCCAGGGCGGGGGGGAUGGCGUCUCCCCGACUCCACCUGAGGGACUGGCUCCUGGGGUGGAAGCAGGGAAAGGCCUGGAGAUGAGGAAGCUGGUUCUCUCGGGGUUCUUGGCCAGCGAAGAGAUCUACAUUAACCAGCUGGAAGCCCUGUUGCUGCCCAUGAAACCCCUGAAGGCCACCGCCACCACCUCCCAGCCCGUGCUCACCAUCCAGCAGAUCGAGACCAUCUUCUACAAGAUCCAGGACAUCUAUGAGAUCCACAAGGAGUUCUAUGACAACCUGUGCCCCAAGGUGCAACAGUGGGACAGCCAGGUCACCAUGGGCCACCUCUUCCAGAAGCUGGCCAGCCAGCUCGGUGUGUACAAAGCGUUUGUCGAUAACUAUAAAGUCGCUCUGGAGACAGCUGAGAAGUGCAGCCAGUCCAACAACCAGUUCCAGAAGAUCUCAGAGGAACUCAAAGUGAAAGGUCCCAAGGACUCCAAGGACAGCCACACGUCUGUCACCAUGGAAGCUCUGCUCUACAAGCCCAUUGACCGGGUCACUCGGAGCACCCUAGUCCUACACGACCUGCUGAAGCACACACCUGUGGACCACCCCGACUACCCGCUGCUGCAGGAUGCCCUCCGCAUCUCCCAGAACUUCCUGUCCAGCAUCAACGAGGACAUCGACCCCCGCCGGACUGCAGUGACAACGCCCAAGGGGGAGACGCGACAGCUGGUGAAGGACGGCUUCCUGGUGGAAGUGUCAGAGAGCUCCCGGAAGCUGCGGCACGUCUUCCUCUUUACAGAUGUCCUACUGUGUGCCAAGCUGAAGAAGACCUCUGCAGGGAAGCACCAGCAGUAUGACUGUAAGUGGUACAUCCCCCUGGCCGACCUGGUGUUUCCAUCCCCCGAGGAGUCUGAGGCCAGCCCCCAGGUGCACCCCUUCCCAGACCAUGAGCUGGAGGACAUGAAGAUGAAGAUCUCUGCCCUCAAGAGUGAAAUCCAGAAGGAGAAAGCCAACAAAGGCCAGAGCCGGGCCAUCGAGCGCCUGAAGAAGAAGAUGUUUGAGAAUGAGUUCCUGCUGCUGCUCAACUCCCCCACAAUCCCGUUCAGGAUCCACAAUCGGAAUGGAAAGAGUUACCUGUUCCUACUGUCCUCGGACUACGAGAGGUCAGAGUGGAGAGAAGCAAUUCAGAAACUACAGAAGAAGGAUCUCCAGGCCUUUGUCCUGAGCUCAGUGGAGCUCCAGGUGCUCACAGGAUCCUGUUUCAAGCUUAGGACUGUACACAACAUUCCUGUCACCAGCAAUAAAGACGACGAUGAGUCUCCAGGACUCUAUGGCUUCCUUCAUGUCAUCGUCCACUCUGCCAAGGGAUUUAAGCAAUCAGCCAACCUGUACUGUACCCUGGAGGUGGAUUCCUUCGGCUAUUUUGUCAGCAAAGCCAAAACCAGGGUGUUCCGGGACACAGCGGAGCCCAAGUGGGAUGAGGAGUUUGAGAUCGAGCUGGAGGGCUCCCAGUCCCUGAGGAUCCUGUGCUAUGAGAAGUGCUAUGACAAGACCAAGGUCAACAAGGACAACAAUGAGAUCGUGGACAAGAUCAUGGGCAAAGGACAGAUCCAGCUGGACCCACAAACCGUGGAGACCAAGAACUGGCACACGGACGUGAUUGAGAUGAACGGGAUCAAAGUGGAAUUUUCCAUGAAAUUCACCAGCCGAGAUAUGAGCCUGAAGAGGACCCCGUCCAAAAAGCAGACCGGCGUCUUCGGUGUGAAGAUCAGCGUGGUGACGAAGCGGGAGCGCUCCAAGGUGCCCUACAUCGUCCGGCAGUGUGUGGAGGAGGUGGAGAAGAGGGGUAUCGAGGAGGUUGGCAUCUACAGGAUAUCGGGCGUGGCCACGGACAUCCAGGCGCUCAAGGCCGUCUUCGAUGCCAAUAACAAGGACAUCCUGCUGAUGCUGAGUGACAUGGACAUCAACGCCAUCGCCGGGACGCUCAAGCUGUACUUCCGGGAACUGCCCGAGCCGCUCCUCACGGACCGACUCUACCCAGCCUUCAUGGAGGGCAUCGCCCUGUCAGACCCUGCUGCCAAGGAAAACUGCAUGAUGCACCUGCUCCGCUCCCUGCCCGACCCCAACCUCAUCACCUUCCUCUUCCUGCUGGAACACUUGAAAAGGGUUGCCGAGAAGGAGCCCAUCAACAAAAUGUCACUUCACAACCUGGCUACCGUGUUUGGACCCACGUUACUGAGACCCUCAGAAGUGGAGAGCAAAGCACACCUCACCUCGGCUGCGGACAUCUGGUCCCAUGACGUCAUGGCGCAGGUCCAGGUCCUCCUCUACUACCUGCAGCACCCCCCCAUUUCCUUCGCAGAACUCAAGCGGAACACACUGUACUUCUCCACCGACGUGUAGCCCGAGGCAGGGUGGCUGCGGGCGGGUGGUGGAACCAGCCCCUCCAGCCUGGGGUCCAACUCAGACUUGAAAGACUGCAAUAGAAAACUCCCAAACCCAGCACUCCAGACUCGAGGGAAGCCAGCUUCCAAGAACUGGAAUGCGUACGUCUUUUGUGCCACCUUGUACAAAGCCGGCUGCCCAGCCCCAGCCUCACCACCGCAUCCCACCUCCUGCCCUCCAUACCUCUAGUUGUGUCUGAUGCUCCGUGCUGUUCGGGAAUUGUUUUAUGUACACUUGUCAGGCAGAAAAGGUAGUGACCGGCCCGGCGUGGGCACACAGACAGCCCGCUUUGUUCUUUCAUUUCCUCCAGCACUUUCUUUCCGCCUGAGUCCAGCCCAAGGCCUUUUAUUUUGCGCUGUGUAACUGCUGCCAGCUUCUCUCUUGGCCCUGCUCCCAGAUGGCGGUCUCCUGGCAGCCUCCCCUCAGUCUUCCUCCACCCGCUCUUCCUUCCCAGCCUGCCUGCAUGCAUGUGCACCCUUGGUCUUCGCUCCAUCGCCUUGAAAGCUCUGAAGAGGCCCUGGGUUGCCGCGGCAGCAGUGGUCUGUUUGAUGCUGCCGUUUGCCGCUGCCGGCCCCUCCUCAGACUCCGCCUUUGGGAGCACACCUGCUUUGCCUUGCUGCCUGUGCAAAUGUUGGACAAGCAGACACACUCACACUCGUCCCCAGCUUAGCACAGAGCUGGAGCGCCCAUUUCUGGAAUUUUCCGUUUGGGAAUCUCCACUUCUGGGGUUUACCUGUUCGGCCUCCUGUCUAUCAGUGAGGCAUCUCUGACUGUUUCUUCUACUGCUUUUCAGUUCCCUUCCCUGCUGUUCUAUUUCCUUUGAGUGUAAAGACUCACAGGUGACCUGCUAUCGAGAUAGCCAGAGGGUCAGGAGAGAAUGGGGGAGGAGGCGGUCAGGCUGCUGAGGAAACACCACAGGCUGAACGGGGGAGGAAUGCACAUGCCACGCUGGGUGUCCCGGGUCGCGGGGAGGCAGCUCAGCUCUUAGGAGCAAGUUGUGGGGGCUUUUCAAGAGGGGCCAGGCUUCCUGGAGGGUGACUGAUGUGGCCGAAGCAGGUGUCCAGGCAGGUAGGCUGCAGCCAGGAGCUCCCUGGCACCGCAGGACCUCGUGGUACUCUUGCCUUAGAUUUUACACACACUCCACAGCCAAGCACUGCCACGGUCCUCCAGGACCUGGGAAGCAAAGGCACAGGCCCACGGUGGCCAGCCAUUGUGGUGCCGCCCCAGCUUCUGGAUACAGCCUUUUGGGUAAACACUGGGAACUCCAGAAGUUGUGGGGAGAGUGGGGAAUCAGACAGCCGCCUCUAGGGGCUGGGUUCUGCUGGGGCCUCCUUGUUGGUGCUGUAGGCACCCGCCAGGGAGCAGGGACCCGACUUGCAGACGCAUUGCCCGGUACUAGGAAGGAGUGAGGUGUGUUCCCACCGUACACUUCCCACACGAGCUGCGGCUGCCAGCCUCGGGCCAUCAGCCUAGGAGAGCAGAUGCAGCUCCAGGGGCUCGACUUAUAGCCAGUUACAGCUCCCCGGCUCUUCUGUGUGGCAGAGCGUCGUUUCCGGGCCCUCAGGGCUGGGGAGCUCAGUUCCCAUUGCUUGUGCUCAGGGCUGAGUCUUAAAGAAGGGUUUGCCGGCCCUAACGCUGCAGCGCGUGCGCGGUGAGAGGCCCUUUUUGAGCCUGUUUACUCCUGUGGCCUUGGGCAGAACAGUAAAUACUCUGUGCACGGAGGAAAGACAUGCCCAAGAGGAAGGAAGUACUGACCAUCGGCUGCCUGUGAGCAGCUUAGCAAGGAGCCCUUGCUCCCUGGGAAAGGCGGUGAACUUGAGUCUAAAGAUGCAGUGCCUGGCCCUUCCUAAGGUCCCUGCCUGGCAUCCGAGUGUCGGUGUGUGGCACAGAAGGCUCCUGCUUGCUUCCAAAGUGAUGGACAGGAAGGGGCAGAGUGAGUCACGGCCCAGACUGGGCACCUUCGCGUCUCAGCCUCAGGGAGCCCCACAGCCCCAAGCUCGCUGAGGCAACGUGAGAACAGGCUAUGGGAAGGCUGCAAAGGCUGAGAAAUGCAAAGGCUCAUAUUUAUAAAUCCCACCCCCAGAGUGGGGAGGGUCAGGUGCCAGACCUGGACUAAACUGCACCAAGGAAACACCCAGCAGGGUCUCCUGUGAGCCGGGGACCAUGCAGCCCGAAACCUCCAGUCACUGCGCCCGGCAGGAGUCAGGAGCCAGGGACUGUGCAGCCUGGAACCUCCAGUCACUGUGCCCAGCAGGGUGGGCUGUGCCCAGCAGGAGUCAGGCUAAGAAACGCCAGGUCUGCCUGUUCUUGCUGGGCAAUGGCUGAUGGCUGCCAGUUUCUGCUGAUACACAGGUAGGAUGGGACCCUUCAUGAAUAUCUGACUUUAAUAAGUUGGUAAGGAUAUAUUUUUUUGUCUAUGUUCUGUUUCAACUUAUGUAGAUUAUUAUAAAUUGAUGUAAACCACGUGAGAGGAAAAUGUUAAUAAAAAAUGCAAAGCCCCAUCAUUUGCACAAAACUCA